AAGCUAAGGCAGCAGGACCUGGAGCCUCCUGCUUUGGAGUGGUUCUUCAAUACUGCUGCUGCUUACGCGCCGGGAAACUGGGAAGGCUGGUGAGCGAGAAGGCAAGGUAAGGUCUCUGAUUUACGGGGGCAUGCCAGUUAAUCCUCCUGAAUGAGGAAGAAAUGAAAGGAAGAGGAGCUUGAGAGUCCCUUGGCUUUGUCUUCUGAGAUGAGGCUUUUAAAAUGAACCAGGAGUCUGGCUGGCCAGUUUUGCAAACUUCUUGUUCAGAAGAACCCCUUAGAGGCAGCUGAACAUAUAGGGCACAUUUUCAAAAGCUGGGAAAGACAGACCCCUUUCACCUAUCCCUAGAGAAAGAUGGUAUGGAGCAAGGCAGGAGGAGUUAAAACCAGCUUCCUGGCCCAGAGAGGUGGCUUACACCUGUAAUCCCAACACUUUGGGAAGCCAGGGCAUGAGGAUUGUUUGAGCCCAGGAGUUUGUAACUUGUGACCAUCCUGGGCAACAUAGUGAGACCCUGUCUCUACAAAAAAAAAAAAAAAAAAAAAAAAAAAAAAAGCCAAGCAUGGUGGUGCACACCUGUGGUCUCAGCUUCUCAGGAGGCUGAGGCAGAAGGAUCACUUGAGCCCAGGAGGUGGCGGUUGCAGUGAGCCGUGAUUGUACCACUGCACUCCAGCCUGGGUGACAGAGCAAGACCCUGUCUCAAAAACAACAACAACAAAAAACAGCUUCCUCUGCUCAGGGUCCGUCCAAAAGGGCAUCUCUGAGAAUUACAGGCCACUGGCUUUUAACCUGACAUUUCAAAACUGUGCCCCACACCCAAGGGGUUUCUGCAGUCCUCUCAAAGGAUACUGAAUUAGGAUUUAGGGAGAAGGAGAGACCCAGCUUUGGGAGAUUUGAUGUCAGAACUGUGUUUUCUGUGUGUUCCAGUGUGACAGGAAGUCCCUUCCUGGAGCUUAUCCUCUCGCAUUCGGGGUGCCUGGCCCAGGGAGCUCCUUGAUUCCUAAAUUCCUGCUGGGAAACGGGACAGGUUUCAGCCUCUGAGGCUCACAGUCCUAAUUGCUGCCGGCUGGUUUGGCUUUUACCAGGGUGACAGUUCUCUGUCUCCAAGGAAUGAAUUCAGUGGCCCUUGUCCCCUUCCCCUAGUUGGCUCAUGGCUUUUGCCUUUAAUGACUGCUACGUAGGGUCUGAAGAAAACCCAAACACCAUAUUUCCUGGCAAUUCUGAGCAGCACAGGGUGGGGCAGCACAAGUUAUCAAAUUAAAUUCUCAAACACUGGCUGCUCCGCACCAUUGCCUUGCUUUAGUCCUGCUACAGCAGUAGACAAAGCGAGUCUGCUUUGAGCUUUAUGGUUUUUUGCCAAAGUCCAUACUAGAUGGCGCAUGCUCUCCAAACUUGGCUUUGUCCAUCAAGGUUCAAGAAAACAAUGGUCAGACAUGUUCCUCUUAACAAACAGUAUGUCCCCAAACAGCAAAAAUGCAUACAGUCCUUUCUGGGUGAAUUUUUAAAUCUUACAUAAAUCCAUCAACCCCAUCCUUUUUCCUUUGCCUCUUGGGAGAAAUUAAUCUAGCUUUACAUUAAUUAUGCAUGUUAUCAGAUUUCAAGCUCCUUGAGAGCAGGUAUUUUAAUUCUAUAAAGCCUCUACGUGGCCUUGGACAUGGGUAGGUGCUUAAUUACCCAAGAUGCUCCUUGAAUACAGAUGGUACACGACCUACACAGACUUAGAUCUUUACCACUUCCCCCCUCUCCCCACCCUGACUUGCUCAAUCCUGAAGGAACUGGAGACGUCUAAGUGUCUGAGGUUCACGCUUCCACACAGAAGCUUGGGUCUGUGUGGGAGGGAAAAAGGAAGCCAUCUGUCCGCAGGCCAGACCAGGCCACACCCUGCUAGCACCCAGAACCCUUUGUCCCAGGCCCAGCCCUGCCAUUUUACUUUCCUUGCAUCUGGAAAGCACAGGGAAUAUAGUAGUGACAAAAGAAGGAAGGGUUGUUUGAGUUUAAGAAUAGUUUACUCUAAAAAAAAAAAAAAAAAAAAAAAAAGGACAAAAGCCAAAGAGAAGGUCAAAGUUGACUGUGGAGAAGGCCUUGCAAGCAGGGAACUUGGGAAGAAUUGGAAUGAGAGUGAGAGAAGGCAACUGAGUUUGGAAAUAUUUUUUCUGACUAGCUUUUCUUUCCAAAUGCCACUGAACUUAGAUUGGUUUAGGAAGGGUUGUAGUACAUCAAAGUGGCUAGAAGCACAGGUUUGGGGAUCAGAUAAGGAUUUCAUUCUAGAGUGUGAUCUUGUACAAGUUAUUCAGCCUUUGCAAACCUCAGAUUCACACAAUGUAAGAUGAAGAAACUCACCUUCUGAAAAUUAGAGAUAACAUAUGCAAAGUGAAUCAAUACAGGGCUUAACAUAUUUAUCACCCCUUUGGUAAAUAACCAUGACGAUUACCAGAGCUCUUAAGGGCAAUGGCAGGUGGGAAGCAGAACUCAUGGGUGGUAAUCCCCAGGCCAGCCAGGCUCACCAUGUGCACUUGGACAAGUCCUUGCCCCCAUCAUUGUGAAAUGGUGCAGGGAUGCACCAUGAGGGUGUGGCAGGAUGGCUGACAACAGACUGGGAAGCAGCUCGGCAGAAAAACUGGAUUGAUGCCCACUAUGGCAAGAGAUAUCAUCUCCCCUCUUGUUCUGUGAUGUUUCAGUCCUGGAAAGACAAGCAUCAUGCCUCUGACCAGUGCCUUCAGGGCUGUGGACAACGACCCUGGGAUCAUUGUCUGGAGAAUAGAGGUGAGCUGGGCUGGAGGCACCUUACUUGUGACCACUGGCAUCUGGAAGCAGUCUGGCUGCCUGGGGCUGCUAGGCAACAGCCCGCCAGCACCCCUUAGCCUAUGGUUUGAGGAGAAUGAGAGGCAGCAUCAAAGUACCUAUUUCCCAUCCUUCACCUCUCCUGGGUGCUCAAAGCAGGUGGUUGGCAGGUGGAGGAAAUGUUCAGCCCCGAAGAACAGGGCUCCAGACAAAAACAGGCUUGUCCUUUAGCCAGCCACCUGCUCAGUGAGUCUGCACUUGCAGGAAACACCCUGGAAAGACAGGUGGGACCUACUCAGCAGACUCCUGGCAGCUUCCAUCAGAGAAAUGGAACAUGUCUUCCACGGGGCACCCUGGCUCCUACAAAAUAUGGGGAGAGGAGGGGGAGUCAGCUCUCCAGCAAGCCUCGCAGAGAUUGUGAGUCCCAGGUCACUUCCACUGUUUGAAGGCUUCCAGUUUCCUUAAAAACUAACAGAAAAUGGAGCUGGCGCUGGUGCCUGUGAGCGCCCACGGCAACUUCUAUGAGGGGGACUGCUACGUCAUCCUCUCGACCCGGAGAGUGGCCAGUCUCCUAUCCCAGGACAUCCACUUCUGGAUCGGGAAGGACUCCUCCCAGGAUGAGCAAAGCUGCGCAGCCAUAUAUACCACACAGCUGGACGACUACCUGGGAGGCAGCCCUGUGCAGCACCGAGAGGUCCAGUACCAUGAGUCAGACACUUUCCGUGGCUACUUCAAGCAGGGCAUCAUCUACAAGCAGGGGGGUGUCGCCUCUGGGAUGAAGCACGUGGAGACCAAUACCUACGACGUGAAGCGGCUGCUACAUGUGAAAGGGAAAAGAAACAUCAGGGCUACCGAGGUGGAAAUGAGCUGGGACAGUUUCAACCGAGGUGAUGUCUUCUUGCUGGACCUUGGGAAAGUCAUCAUCCAAUGGAAUGGCCCAGAGAGCAACAGUGGGGAGCGCCUGAAGGCUAUGCUUCUGGCAAAGGAUAUUCGAGACAGGGAGCGAGGGGGCCGUGCUAAAAUAGGAGUGAUCGAGGGAGACAAGGAGGCAGCCAGCCCAGAGCUGAUGAAGGUCCUUCAGGACACCCUUGGCCGACGCUCCAUUAUCAAGCCUACAGUCCCUGAUGAGAUCAUAGAUCAGAAGCAGAAAUCAACUAUCAUGUUGUAUCAUAUCUCAGAUUCAGCUGGGCAGCUGGCAGUCACAGAGGUAGCAACAAGGCCUCUGGUCCAGGACUUACUGAACCAUGAUGACUGCUACAUCCUGGACCAAAGUGGAACCAAAAUCUACGUGUGGAAAGGAAAAGGAGCCACAAAGGCUGAAAAACAGGCAGCCAUGUCUAAAGCGCUGGGCUUCAUCAAGAUGAAGAGCUACCCCAGCAGCACCAAUGUGGAGACCGUCAACGAUGGUGCUGAGUCGGCCAUGUUCAAGCAGCUGUUCCAGAAGUGGUCAGUAAAGGACCAGACCAUGGGCCUGGGGAAAACGUUCAGCAUUGGUAAAAUUGCUAAAGUUUUCCAGGAUAAAUUUGAUGUGACUCUGCUACACACCAAGCCAGAGGUAGCUGCCCAGGAAAGAAUGGUCGAUGAUGGCAACGGAAAAGUUGAGGUCUGGAGAAUUGAGAACCUGGAGCUGGUCCCUGUGGAGUAUCAAUGGUAUGGCUUCUUUUAUGGGGGAGACUGUUAUCUGGUCCUCUACACAUACGAGGUAAAUGGGAAGCCACAUCACAUCUUGUACAUCUGGCAGGGCCGCCACGCCUCACAGGAUGAGCUGGCAGCCUCAGCAUACCAGGCAGUGGAGGUGGAUCGGCAGUUUGAUGGGGCUGCUGUGCAGGUUCGAGUCAGGAUGGGAACGGAGCCACGCCACUUCAUGGCCAUCUUCAAAGGGAAGCUAGUUAUCUUUGAGGGUGGGACUUCCAGGAAGGGAAAUGCCGAGCCUGACCCUCCAGUAAGACUCUUCCAAAUUCAUGGAAAUGACAAAUCUAACACCAAAGCAGUGGAAGUUCCAGCCUUUGCCUCCUCCCUAAACUCCAAUGAUGUCUUUCUGCUGCGAACUCAGGCAGAGCACUACCUGUGGUAUGGCAAGGGGUCUAGUGGGGAUGAGCGGGCAAUGGCUAAGGAGCUGGCCAGCCUUCUCUGUGAUGGCAGCGAGAACACUGUGGCCGAGGGCCAGGAGCCAGCCGAGUUCUGGGACCUACUGGGAGGGAAAACUCCCUAUGCCAAUGAUAAAAGGUAUGGGAACACAGCCUCCCCCUCUUCUGGGCUCCCCCUGCCUGCCAGGCUUGUGAAUUGCACAAAGGCUAAAACCUCAGUUUUAAAAACAUUUCUAAGCAGCUUGAUGCCCUUAAAUGGACUAUAUUGCAGACUUCAGCAGGAAAUCCUAGAUGUCCAGUCUCGUCUCUUUGAAUGUUCCAAUAAGACCGGCCAAUUCGUUGUCACUGAGAUCACAGACUUCACCCAGGAUGACCUGAACCCUACUGACGUGAUGCUCCUAGAUACCUGGGACCAGGUGUUCUUGUGGAUUGGGGCUGAGGCCAAUGCCACGGAGAAGGAGAGUGCCCUUGCCACAGCACAGCAGUACCUGCACACUCACCCCAGCGGCCGAGAUCCCGACACACCAAUCCUGAUCAUUAAGCAGGGGUUUGAGCCUCCCAUCUUCACAGGCUGGUUCCUAGCCUGGGACCCUAACAUUUGGAGUGCAGGAAAAACAUAUGAACAAUUAAAAGAAGAGCUGGGAGAUGCUGCUGCUAUCAUGCGAAUCACUGCUGACAUGAAGAAUGCAACCCUCUCCCUGAAUUCUAAUGACAGUGAGCCAAAAUAUUACCCUAUAGCAGUUCUGUUGAAAAACCAGAAUCAGGAGCUGCCUGAGGAUGUAAACCCUGCCAAAAAGGAGAAUUACCUCUCUGAACAGGACUUUGUGUCUGUGUUUGGCAUCACAAGAGGGCAAUUUGCAGCUCUGCCUGGCUGGAAACAGCUCCAAAUGAAGAAAGAAAAGGGGCUUUUCUAAAGCAAGAAGGCCUAUACCUAUUGCAAGGCCACAGAAAAGAGCAGAUAGUGCCAAUAUCAGGAAAUAAUUUAUCCACCAAUUUCUGCCUGACAUUCAGCUACUUAAUUUAGAUAUAAUAGAGUCUGCAAAUCACGGCAUGUUCUCCAUUUUUUCUCAUCCUUGCAUUCCUUGCUUGUUAUAUACCUAAAAUGUUAACCAUAUAGUUUUUGGGUUUUGUGGCCCUCUAGCUAAAGCCUCAGCAGAAAGCACUAAAACUGCAUAAAUCUGGAGAAAUCAAAAGAAAGAGAACCAAAAAACAAUGCUUAAAAUGUUUAAUAACUUUAUGUUUAAUAUUAUACCAGGACCUACCUUUGUUUUCAAUUUUAAGAUGAUUAUUUCUAAAAUCUAUUUAGCCUGUAAAUCAUUGAAAUCAUAUAUGCACUCCAUAGGCAAAAUCCAAAUACCCAGAUCUGUAAUGUGUCAAAGCAUUUUUCACUUUUCAAAUAAAGAUACCUAUAAUGAA